AUGAAUAAGGAGAAUCACUCCUUGAUAGCUGAGUUCAUCCUCACAGGAUUUACAUAUCAUCCAAAGCUGAAGACUGUUCUGUUUGUGGUGUUCUUUGCCAUCUAUCUGAUCACCAUGGUGGGGAACAUUGGUUUGGUGGCAUUGAUUUAUAUAGAGCAACGUCUUCACACACCAAUGUACAUAUUUUUAGGCAACCUAGUUCUGAUGGAUUCCUGCUGUUCCUCUGCUAUUACUCCCAAGAUGUUAGAGAACUUCUUUUCUGAGGACAAAAGGAUUACCCUGUAUGAAUGUAUGGCACAAUUUUAUUUUCUCUGUCUUGCUGAAACUACAGACUGCUUUCUUCUGGCGGCAAUGGCCUAUGACUGCUAUGUGGCCAUAUGCAACCCACUGCAGUACCACACCAUGAUGUCCAAGACACUCUGCAUUCAGAUGACUGCAGGAGCCUACCUAGCUGGCAACCUGCAUCCCAUGAUUGAAGUAGAGUUUCUGUUGAGGUUAACUUUCUGUGGGUCUCAUCAAAUCAAUCAUUUUUUCUGUGAUGUUCUUCCAUUAUAUAGACUUUCUUGUAUUAACCCUUAUAUCAAUGAAUUGGUGUUAUUUAUCUUGGCAGGAUCAAUUCAAAUCUUUACUAUAGUCUUAGUUUCUUAUUUCUACAUCCUUUUCACAAUAUUUACAAUGAAAUCCAAGGAGGGAAGAGGCAAAGCUUUAUCUACUUGUGCAUCUCACUUUCUCUCUGUGUCAAUAUUCUGUGAUUCCCUUCUCUUCAUGUAUGCUCGACCAGGUGCAGUUAAUGAAGGGGAUAAAGAUAUACCUGUUGCUAUAUUUUAUACUUUAGUUAUUCCUUUAUUAAAUCCUUUUAUUUAUAGCCUAAGAAAUAAGGAAGUAAUAAAUAUUAUGAAAAAAAUUAUGAAGAAGAGAAAAUUUUGUCACAUUCUGAAACAAAUGUCAUCCCCUCUGGCAACUUGA